GUAGCGGGCGACCUAGGCCGCGGGACCCGGACGGAGGUAGAGGCCAGGGCAGCGCGUCCGGGAGCGGAGUCCGCGCCCGCCGCCGCCAUGCCGGACAGCUGGGACAAGGAUGUGUACCCUGAGCCCCCGCGCCGCACGCCGGUGCAGCCCAAUCCCAUCGUCUACAUGAUGAAAGCGUUCGACCUCAUCGUGGACCGACCCGUGACCCUCGUGAGAGAAUUUAUAGAGCGGCAGCACGCAAAGAACAGGUAUUACUACUACCACCGGCAGUACCGCCGCGUGCCAGACAUCACUGAGUGCAAGGAGGAGGACAUCAUGUGCAUGUAUGAAGCCGAAAUGCAGUGGAAGAGGGACUACAAAGUCGACCAAGAAAUUAUCAACAUUAUGCAGGAUCGGCUCAAAGCCUGUCAGCAGAGGGAAGGACAGAACUACCAGCAGAACUGUAUCAAGGAAGUGGAGCAGUUCACCCAGGUGGCCAAGGCCUACCAGGACCGCUAUCAGGACCUGGGGGCCUACAGUUCUGCCAGGAAGUGCCUGGCCAAACAGAGGCAGAGGAUGCUGCAAGAGAGAAAAGCUGCAAAAGAGGCCGCCGCUGCCACCUCCUGAGGCAGCUGUGGGUGCCCCUGCUGUGUGGCUCUGUAUGACUGUUGCUGAAAUAUAAAGCCCUGCAACCUG